AGCAAAGACCUGAGGACCUUCAAGAGUGUGGCCCCAGCGGGCUCCAGCCUCCGAGCCUAGCUCGGGAGGCGUGGUGUAGAAAAUGGCAGACUAGGGCAUCCAUGAAGACCGGGCGGCCCCAAGCCGAGAGGCAUGGCAAAACAGGGGUUGCAGGUGGCUGUUCUGGCAGAGCGAGGAGGAUGGAUUUGAAGAAGACAGGCAUGCAGGGGAGACCUUUGAGGGGAAUGUGUCAACAGCCAAGGGGGGCGGGGCGCCGGGGAGGUCUGGAUGAAGUGGGAAUGAGGAUGGAGUGCAGAGUGCCUGGAGAAGUGUUCAGGAGGGAAGGCGAGGCAUCGGGACGAGGGGCUGGGCGGUCGCGCCAUCUCUGCGAUAGACAAUAAUCGGGUCAACACGCGGCGAGUGGCGGUGCGCGCGGGGCCAACCGCGUGGAGCUGUCGGGAGGGCGAUAGGAUGGGCGCGCCCGGGCUGCAGGCGGGGAGCCGGAGGUGGGAGGUGCCUCUUGAGAGUGGCUCUCCACCGCUGACAGCAAACGAGCUGGUCCGGACGGAGGACAGAGGGGGAAGAAACGGAGGGAGUCGCUGGGGGACGGCGACGAGUGGGAUCCGGGCGGGUGGGACUGGGCGCAAAGGACCGCGCCGACGCCGCAUGGCUGCCGGGAAUUCAGCUCCCCCGGCCAGGUUGAGCGGGCCCCGGGGCCCGGAGCGGGCGUCGGCAUCUCCGGCCUCCCCGCGGGGCUGCAGGCAGGCGGCGCCCCGAGCGCACCCCGCGCGAGCAGGCGCGGAACAGCGGACCCAGGCCGGGCCUUCCCGCAGCUUUUCUGGCCGCCUCGGAGGGCAGGGUCCCAGCGCGGCCCGAGGCGCCUCUUGCCAGCGGCCCGACCUCCUGCCCUCCCGGCCCCCUCCAGGCUCCCCGCACGUGCAGGCCCGGCGACGUCACUGCGGCUCUGACGCGCUCUUGGAGGCCCGGGCGGAGGCGGCGCGGCGCGGGCUUCCUCCGGGAGGUCCCGGUCCCGGCAGCCCGCGGCCGCGUCCUUGGCCCUCCUCCGGGGGAACCUCGUUCAUUCCAAACUCUGGAAGGCCGGCUGUCCUUCGGUUACUGAUAAGGACGCGAGCUCUUGGUAAAAGAUUUGAACAAUGCCCGGAAAGAAAUAGCUGGACCUAAGAAACAGACUAAUAAUAGCUGCCAGCUAGAGCUCCACUCGUGUGCUCAGCGCCUUUAGGAACAAUAAUAACGACCACAGCCAUAGUAGCCACCAUUUAUUGAGCGCUUACUCUGUGCCAGGUGCUGUGUUAAGCGCUUUGCAGGCAACAACCCUCGGAGGUAAGUACCAUUAUCAUCCCUAUUUUGCAGGAAACCCGGGCACAGAGAGGUUAAGUAACUUGCCCCAGGGCACACAGCUAGCUGAUGUCAGUGCCAGAAUUCCAACCGCGGCUGUCGGACCCCAUGCCAUCCUCAUGUCAACCCACUAAGGACGGGAUCCUUCUGUCCAUCUUAAAGAUGAGGCAACUAAGGCACAUGGAAAUUUAAGUAUAAUACCUUGCCCAAGGUCACCUAGCUGGAAAAUGGACGAGACAGAAAGCGAACCCAGGGCUCCUUUCUGUACGCAGAACCCGCGGUCUUGGCCAUAGGCGAUGCCACUUCCGACAGCCCAGCAGGGUCUGGCCCUGGGUCCCAGAGGCGCAGCCCCUGCGGGGUUUGGAUGGGUUCCUGCGGCCUCCGAUCCGCUGGUGAAUUGGGUGUGUCUGAGCAUCGUCCCCGCUCAGCCCGCAGGCGUAGGAUAGGGAGGCGUCUCCGGGAAUCUACUCCGGGACGGGUCCGCGGUCCUCAGUCGGGAUGGAGCGGGGGCGGAGGCAGCCGGAGGGAACUGGAGUCCCCAUUGCAGAACUGCGGGGCCGGGCUCUGGGCUGGGCGCCUGCCCCGCGCGGCCGGCAGAGGGCGCUGCCGCACACGCCUUGGAUCUCACUGUCACUGGGACCUCGGGGCAGGCUGACGUCGGCCUGCAGACGCCUGGACUCAGAACCCCGAAGCAAGAAGCUUCCCUUCCUGGUGGCUGCCAUCCCUCAGGCCCACCAUUUCAGCCCUGGACCUGCUUUCCCUGACCACUUUUCCCCAUCUUCUGUGCUCCUGCCAUCCCACCACUGGCCUUCAAGACUUCCCCAGUCCCUGCACAGCGGGUUUUGUCAUCUGCUGAGAGGCGCGGACACUGAUUCCCAUCCCAUUAAAAGGCCUAGAUGUCUGCAAGUCAAAUUCAGCCUUGCUUCCCCUUCUCGCCCUCUGGUGAUUUAAAAUAGGGAUACAUCAUCUACUUGGAAUAAAUGACUAAUUUUUCUCUUCUCCAAAA